GUUAGAUUCUACCUCUGUCACCCAGGCGGGAGUGCAGUGGCAUGAUCUCGGCUCACUGCAACCUCCGCCUCCUGGGUUCAAGCAAUUCUCCUGUCUCAGCCUCCCGAGUAGCUGAGACUACAGGCAUGUGCCACCAGGCAUGGCUAAUUUUUGUAUUUUUAGUGGAGACAGGGUUUCACUCUAUUAGGCUGGUCUGGAACUCCCGACCUCAGGUGAUCCACCUGCCUUUGUCUCCCAAAGUGCUGGGAUUACAGGCAUGAGUGACGGUGCCCAGCCAUUCAUGACGUGUUUAUACAAAUAUAACUUUAGCAAACAUUUAGCAUAACUAUCAAAAUUACAAAUCAUAUUAAAUUUGUAUAAAUGUAUGCAAUUUUUGGAACACGUAUAUCAACAACAUACCCAUAAAUAUAACUGAGAUGAGAUCUAAUGUCACCUCACUUGACAGUGCCCUCCCAUGCAGUAUCGCCACAUUUGACAAUGCCUGCCCAUUUAAUCUACCAAAUAAAUCGAAUCACUUAAUACCUCUACAAGAUGAGAGAUACAUUCUUUAGACUCCCCAAGGGAUGCAGCUGAAAAAAUCCCAAAGUUAGUUUUAAGCCAAAAAGACUUGAUUUAGGAUUUUGACACUGGAGAAACCCAUCAAAGACGUCAAGUUUGAAAACACUUGAUCAAAACAGAAUCACAGGUCACUAUUAAAAGAGUAUUAAUUUAACCAGAGACUUCCAAAGCAAUACAGAAACUUACAUGGAUAUAAAAACCUUAACCCUUUUAAAGGUCAGAUUUGCUAAGUGAUCAAAAGGGGUACUUGAAUUGAAUCGACACAGGAAGAGUGUGUACAGGGUUAUGAGUGUAGGCAGAUGGUUACUUUGGUCAUAUCUCCAUUUGCCACCUGAUUACACAUGAGAAUGCCAUCUUUACUCACCAGAAAGCCAGUAUUAUAGGAGGUGUAGGAGGCAUUCUUGGACUUGAAACAAGAACAUUGUUGUGUAGAAAUUUCAUUGACUGUGUUAAAAUUAUUCUCCAUGGGCUGGAGAACACAUAACAUGGCCUUUAGAAUGAGACGGGCAUUGAUUGGAUGCAAGGUCUCCACACUUACUAGCCGUGUGACAUUGGACAGAGUGCUUCAUCAUUCCGAGACUCAGUUUUUAAAGGAAAAACAACUAACUACCUUGCAAGCUUGCUAGCAGGUUUAAGUGUAAUAAUGUGUGGGAAUGACUGCACCGUGACUAACACGUGGUGACGGCUUAAUUAAUGUUAACCCUUAUCAUUAUCGUAUAAGAAUGUGAGUUGCAUAAGAGAGGAAUCCUGUCAGUUUGUUCUCUGCUGUGUCCCCAAGACCAUGAAUCAUGGCUGGCACGUAGUAGGCUUUUAAUAAUAUUUGUUCAACAAGUAUUUGGCAGUCUUGGAGGGCAGAAAAGGAGGUGGGGAAGAUUUUUAAAUAACAUUUUUUAAAAAGUCACAUUGUCCUACAAUAUCGAUUUUUCUUGCAUAUUUAGGAAAUUGAGGGUUUUUUCCUAAAACAUGCGGACAUAUGGGAAAUAUGAUGCAACAUUUGCACUAAUGUUUCAGACACAGUUAGAGGUUUCCAAGAGAUUUUGUGCUGGGGAGGCUGCUUGCUACAAGCUCCCAAAGCUCUGGGAGGACAUAGUAUUCAUUCCUCCCUCAGCAGAAGCGGUGAGGCAAGAAGCUCUGGGGAGCACCCAGCCUUGGACUUUUAGCAUAGUGUGUCAGGUCUUCAUAGUUUGGGCCCAGGGCACAGAGAAGUCACAGCUCUCUGGCAUCCUGUGACCUUUACCCUCUUUGCCAAGGGAAAAUGUGGCCCACCAAAGCAAGAAACUUGAGGGCAUGGGUCACCCCAGCCCUGGCAUCUGCCCAGAGCCCGAGAAGGAAGGAACAAUGAUCCUCCAGCUACCUCACAGGGCUGGCACAGGUGACCACUGCCCUGGCAUCACCCAGCUGUGUCCGGCAGCCUGAACCCCAUCUGUGGGGAUGCGAGGAGGAAAAUACAAAAGCCCUUAGGUGAGCACUGAGAAGGCAGAUGCAGCAGAAACCUCCAGGCCGGAACUACCCAGUCUUGGACCUAUGGUGGAGACAGAGCAUAGCUGGCGAUCAUGUGUACUUACACUCUAAGGUCACCUGGUUGCACUGUGGCCUCAUCUGUGGCUCUGAAAAUGAAGAUUUGGAAGGAGAUCAUCACAGCUAAUGUUUAACAAGCCCCUCCUGUGUGCCAAAUCAUUCACCCCUCACCACAACCGAAUGAGCUAAGGAUUCUCAUUAUAUAUAGUUUAUGGAGAGGGAAGUGCAGACAUAAAGAGGUGAAUUAUCUUACCCAGAUCACACAGCUGAUAAGUGGUGGAGGCAGAAUAGAAUCUAAACAGUGUGGCUCCGGAGCCCACAUGCAUUGAUUCGACAAGUGUUUAUUGAGCACCUGCCACGGACAAGGCCUUGUGUGAUUAAAUAGGGUUAUAAUUAGUAAUAUAAAAAUGAGAAAUCACUAAUGCUUUUUAGACUUAACAUUUUCUUUUUUUGUAGGUUUCAGGCACAGAACUGUAUAUCCAAUAAUAGUGAAAUGGAUCCCACUAAUUAUGACAGAAAUGAUGAUACAUUUAAAUGACUUGGAUGUUUUAUAGGUAUGAUCUCGUGAAACCUUGAGAGAAACUGAAUGACGAAUGAAACUAUUGUUCCUGUUUCACACAGAAGAAAACUGAGGUUGGCACUCAUCAUGAGCCCCUGUUCUCAUUCUGCAAAUGGUGAAGCUCUCUAUUGUCCUGACCCCACAGUUCCUGUCCCAUGACCAGGGCCAGCUCACCAAGGAGCUGCAGCAGCACGUAAAGUCAGUGACAUGCCCAUGCGAGUACCUGAGGAAGGUUAUCAAUACUCUGGCUGACCAUCAUCAUCGUGGGACUGACUUUGGUGGAAGUCCUUGGUUACAUAUUAUUAUUGCGUUUCCGACAAGUUAUAAAGUUGUCAUUACCCUCUGGAUAGUUUACCUUUGGGUGUCUCUCCUGAAGACUAUCUUCUGGUCUCGAAAUGGACAUGAUGGAUCCACGGAUGUACAGCAGAGAGCCUGGAGGUCCAACCGCCGUAGACAGGAAGGGCUGAGGUCCAUUUGUAUGCACACAAAGAAAAGAGUUUCUUCCUUUCGAGGAAAUAAAAUUGGCCUGAAAGACGUCAUUACUCUACGGAGGCAUGUGGAAACAAAAGUUAGAGCUAAAAUCCGUAAGAGGAAGGUGACAACGAAAAUCAACCGUCAUGACAAAAUCAAUGGAAAGAGGAAGACCGCCAGAAAACAGAAAAUGUUUCAACGUGCGCAAGAGUUGCGGCGGCGGGCAGAGGACUACCACAAAUGCAAAAUCCCCCCUUCUGCAAGAAAGGCUCUUUGCAACUGGGUCAGAAUGGCGGCAGCGGAGCAUCGUCAUUCUUCAGGAUUGCCCUACUGGCCCUACCUCACAGCUGAAACUUUAAAAAACAGGAUGGGCCACCAGCCACCUCCUCCAACUCAACAACAUUGUAUAACUGAUAACUCCCUGAGCCUCAAGACACCUCUCGAGUGUCUGCUCACUCCCCUUCCACCCUCAGCGGAUGAUAAUCUCAAGACACCUCCCGAGUGUCUGCUCACUCCCCUUCCACCCUCAGCGGAUGAUAAUCUCAAGACACCUCCCGAGUGUCUGCUCACUCCCCUUCCACCCUCAGCUCCACCCUCAGCUCCACCCUCAGCGGAUGAUAAUCUCAAGACACGUGCCGAGUGUCUGCUCCAUCCCCUUCCACCCUCAGCGGAUGAUAAUCUCAAGACACCUUCCGAGCGUCAGCUCACUCCCCUUCCACCCUCAGCUCCACCCUCAGCAGAUGAUAAUAUCAAGACAACUGCCGAGCGUCUGCGGGGGCCGCUUCCACCCUCAGCGGAUGAUAAUCUCAAGACACCUUCUGAGCGUCAGCUCACUCCCCUUCCACCCUCAGCUCCACCCUCAGCAGAUGAUAAUAUCAAGACACCUGCCGAGCAUCUGCGGGGGCCGCUUCCACCCUCAGCGGAUGAUAAUCUCAAGACACCUUCUGAGCGUCAGCUCACUCCCCUUCCACCCUCAGCUCCACCCUCAGCAGAUGAUAAUAUCAAGACACCUGCCGAGCGUCUGCGGGGGCCGCUUCCACCCUCAGCCGAUGAUAAUCUCAAGACACCUUCUGAGCGUCAGCUCACUCCCCUUCCACCCUCAGCUCCACCCUCAGCAGAUGAUAAUAUCAAGACACCUGCCGAGCAUCUGCGGGGGCCGCUUCCACCCUCAGCGGAUGAUAAUCUCAAGACACCUUCUGAGCGUCAGCUCACUCCCCUUCCACCCUCAGCUCCACCCUCAGCAGAUGAUAAUAUCAAGACAACUGCCGAGCAUCUGCGGGGGCCGCUUCCACCCUCAGCGGAUGAUAAUCUCAAGACACCUUCCGAGCGUCAGCUCACUCCCCUUCCACCCUCAGCUCCACCCUCAGCAGAUGAUAAUAUCAAGACACCUGCCGAGCAUCUGCAGUUCCGCUUCCACCCUCAGCGGAUGAUAAUCUCAAGAGACCUUCCGAGCGUCAGCUCACUCCCCUUCCACCCUCAGCUCCACCCUCAGCAGAUGAUAAUAUCAAGAUACCUGCUGAGCAUCUGCGGGUUCCGCUUCCACCGUCAGCGGAUGAUAAUCUCAAGACACCUUCCGAGCGUCAGCUCACUCCCCUUCCACCCUCAGCUCCACCCUCAGCAGAUGAUAAUAUCAAGACACCUGCCGAGCGUCUGCGGGGGCCGCUUCCACCCUCAGCCGAUGAUAAUCUCAAGACACCUUCCGAGCGUCAGCUCACUCCCCUUCCACCCUCAGCUCCACCCUCAGCAGAUGAUAAUAUCAAGACACCUGCCGAGCGUCUGCGGGGGCCGCUUCCACCCUCAGCCGAUGAUAAUCUCAAGACACCUUCCGAGCGUCAGCUCACUCCCCUUCCACCCUCAGCUCCACCCUCAGCAGAUGAUAAUAUCAAGACACCUGCCGAGCGUCUGCGGGGGCCGCUUCCACCCUCAGCCGAUGAUAAUCUCAAGACACCUUCCGAGCGUCAGCUCACUCCCCUUCCACCCUCAGCUCCACCCUCAGCAGAUGAUAAUAUCAAGACACCUGCCGAGCGUCUGCGGGGGCCGCUUCCACCCUCAGCCGAUGAUAAUCUCAAGACACCUUCCGAGCGUCAGCUCACUCCCCUUCCACCCUCAGCUCCACCCUCAGCAGAUGAUAAUAUCAAGACACCUGCCGAGCGUCUGCGGGGGCCGCUUCCACCCUCAGCCGAUGAUAAUCUCAAGACACCUUCCGAGCGUCAGCUCACUCCCCUUCCACCCUCAGCUCCACCCUCAGCAGAUGAUAAUAUCAAGACACCUGCCGAGCGUCUGCGGGGAGCGUCUGUGGGUUCCGCUUCCACCCUCAGCGGAUGAUAAUCUCAAGACACCUUCCAAACGUCAGCUCACUCCCCUUCCACCCUCAGCUCCACCCUCAGCAGAUGAUAAUAUCAAGACACCUGCCGAGCGUCUGCGGGGGCCGCUUCCACCCUCAGCCGAUGAUAAUCUCAAGACACCUUCCAAACGUCAGCUCACUCCCCUUCCACCCUCAGCUCCACCCUCAGCAGAUGAUAAUAUCAAGACACCUGCCGAGCGUCUGCGGGGGCCGCUUCCACCCUCAGCCGAUGAUAAUCUCAAGACACCUUCCGAGCGUCAGCUCACUCCCCUUCCACCCUCAGCUCCACCCUCAGCAGAUGAUAAUAUCAAGACACCUGCCGAGCGUCUGCGGGGGCCGCUUCCACCCUCAGCGGAUGAUAAUCUCAAGACACCUUCCGAGCGUCAGCUCACUCCCCUUCCACCCUCAGCUCCAACCUCAGCAGAUGAUAAUAUCAAGACACCUGCCGAGCGUCUGCGGGGGCCGCUUCCACCCUCAGCCGAUGAUAAUCUCAAGACACCUCCCUUAGCUACUCAGGAGGCUGAGGCAGAAAAACCACGCAAACCCAAGAGGCAGAGGGCGGCUGAGAUGGAACCACCUCCCGAACCCAAGAGGCGGAGGGUCGGUGACGUGGAACCGUCACGCAAACCCAAGAGGCGGAGGGCCGCUGACGUGGAACCAUCAUCACCCGAACCCAAGAGGCGGAGGGUCGGUGAUGUGGAACCGUCACGCAAACCCAAGAGGCGGAGGGCCGCUGACGUGGAACCAUCAUCACCCGAACCCAAGAGGCGGAGGUUGAGCUGAGAAGAGGCCAGUGCACUCAAGCCUGAGCAAUAAGAAUAAAACCGAGUAGAACAAAAUAAAAAAUUCAAAAAACAAAACAAAACCCACACUCCAAAAACUAACAAAGAAUAAAUAAAUAAUAUAAAAAUAAAAUAAA